GUCAUCUCGGCGCGCCGCUGCCAGGGCUGUACACCUGCUGGCUGCCAUGGCUGAGGUGGGCCGUACCGGGAUCAGCUACCCAGGCGCGCUUCUCCCACAGGGCUUCUGGGCUGCGGUCGAAGUGUGGCUGGAGAGGCCGCAGGUGGCAAACAAACGGCUUUGCGGCGCCCGCCUGGAGGCCCGCUGGAGCGCCGCCCUGCCCUGCGCGGAGGCCCGCGGCCCCGGGACUAGCGCAGGCUCGGAGCAGAAGGAGCGGGGUCCGGGACCCGGCCAGGGUUCCCCCGGAGGGGGCCCGGGUCCCAGGUCGCUAUCAGGACCCGAGCAGGGCACGGCAUGUUGCGAACUUGAGGAGGCCCAGGGCCAGUGCCAGCAAGAGGAGGCACAGAGGGAAGCCGCCUCAGUGCCCCUGAGGGACUCCGGGCACCCCGGCCAUGCUGAAGGAAGGGAGGGCGACUUCCCCGCCGCAGAUCUGGAUUCGCUUUGGGAGGAUUUCUCCCAAAGUCUCGCCCGUGGCAAUUCGGAGUUGCUGGCCUUCCUCACCAGCUCCGGGGCGGGAUCGCAGCCAGAGGCGCAGCGUGAGCUCGACGUGGUUCUCAGAACCGUCAUCCCGAAAACUAGCCCACAUUGCCCCCUUACAACUCCCAGGAGGGAAAUAGUCGUGCAAGAUGUCCUCAAUGGAACCAUAACGUUUUUGCCUUUGGAAGAAGAUGAUGAGGGGAACCUAAAGGUUAAGAUGAGCAAUGUGUAUCAAAUUCAGCUCAGUCAUAGCAAAGAAGAAUGGUUCAUAUCUGUUUUAAUUUUCUGUCCAGAAAGAUGGCAUUCAGAUGGAAUCGUGUAUCCCAAACCCACGUGGCUUGGAGAAGAGUUGCUGGCCAAGUUGGCCAAGUGGUCUGUAGAGAACAAGAAGAGUGACUUUAAAAGCACCCUUUCCCUCAUCUCCAUUAUGAAGUAUAGCAAGGCUUACCAGGAACUUAAAGAGAAGUAUAAGGAAAUGGUUAAGGUGUGGCCUGAAGUCACUGAUCCUGAGAAGUUCGUGUAUGAAGAUGUGGCUAUCGCAGCAUACCUGCUGAUUCUAUGGGAAGAAGAAAGGGCUGAGAGGAGACUAACUGCCAGGCAGUCCUUUGUGGACCUGGGAUGUGGAAAUGGCCUCCUGGUCCACAUCCUGAGCAGUGAGGGGCAUCCAGGCAGAGGGAUUGAUGUCCGAAGAAGAAAAAUCUGGGACAUGUAUGGACCACAAACUCAGUUAGAGGAAGAUGCAAUCACACCCAAUGAUAAGACCCUUUUCCCUGAUGUUGAUUGGUUAAUCGGUAACCAUUCUGAUGAACUCACACCAUGGAUACCUGUCAUUGCAGCCAGGUCUUCCUACAAUUGCCGCUUCUUUGUCCUCCCCUGCUGCUUCUUUGACUUCAUUGGAAGAUACUCCCGGAGGCAGAGUAAGAAGACUCAGUACCGGGAAUACCUUGACUUCAUUAAAGAAGUGGGCUUCACCUGUGGGUUUCACGUGGACGAAGACUGCCUCAGGAUUCCUUCAACCAAAAGAGUCUGUCUCGUUGGAAAAUCCAGAACAUACCCUUCCUCCAGAGAAGCUUCCGUGGAUGAAAAGAGGACUCAGUACAUUAAGAGCAGGCGGGGCUGCCCUGUAAGCCCACCUGGCUGGGAGCUUUCCCCUUCUCCACGCUGGGUUGCUGCUGGCAGUGCUGGUCACUGUGACGGUCAGCAAGCUCUGGACGCCAGGGUCGGGUGUGUAACCAGGGCCUGGGCCGCUGAGCAUGGAGCAGGGCCCCAGGCUGAAGGACCCUGGCUACCUGGAUUUCAUCCCAGAGAAAAGGCUGAGCGUGUGAGGAACUGUGCCGCCCUGCCACGAGAUUUUAUUGACCAAGUGGUUUUGCAAGUAGCGAAUUUACUGUUAGGUGGAAAGCAAUUAAACACAAGAAGUUCUCGAAAUGGGAGUUUGAAGACCUGGAAUGGGGGAGAGAGCCUAUCUCUGGCAGAAGUAGCCAACGAGCUGGACACGGAGACCCUGCGGAGGCUGAAGCGGGAGUGUGGGGGCCUGCAGACGCUGCUCCGGAACAGCCACCAGGUGUUCCAAGAUGCUCACCUGUGAAGAGGGAGAACGUCGCUGUCCGAGCAAAUGUCUCUUCUGUGUCCUUGGCUGCCUUCCUCCUCCUCCUCCCGCCGCCUACUUUGGGGCCCCUUCCUCUUCUCAGCAGUGCCACUGACCAGCCCAGCCUCAUGCACCAUCCCGGCCGUUGCCCUGGAGGGCUGGCAGCUGGCAGGACUCAGAGAGGGCCCAGCCAUCACCCCUCUCUUGAGCAGAUGACAGAGUAACACUGGGAGUUACUAUGGACACUGGAAAAGAGAACACAGAUGCGUCGGAGAUUUUGUAGUUGCAACUCUUCUCUGGUAACCAAAAAACAUCAGGACAUUCAUUGCAAGUGCAACGCUGAGGCUUUGAAGGAACCAAAGAGAUCCUUUGCAGCCCUGAGGACGGAGGGAGGGAGGGAAAAGGGAGUGGGGUGGGAGGGAGGGAGGGAGUCCACUGCAGAAAGUGGCACUGAUCCCUCUGAGCCUCUCCGGCCUCAUGUGUAAGAUGCCAGCUGCCCCGGAGUGGCAGUGGCGAGUGAGUGGCUGUGUAAGGUGCCCAGGCAGGAGCUUGCGGGCAGCCCUGUGUGAAGUGGGCAGCCUUGGGCCGGGUUCCCUAGAAGCAGAGCUGAGAUGGGGAUUCUUGUUCAUGCGAUUGGAGGUGCUUCCUAAGAAGUUGCUCCCUGCCCCAACUCCGAGCCAGGGCAGCACUGACCAUGGGCAACUUUCCCUUGCAGGGGGCACUCCCAGCUGCCGGGGAGGGGCAGUGGCCCUGAAGGGGCCUGGUCAGGACCAACAGUUUUCUUGGCAGUGGUGUGUUUGUCCCCAUUUCGCAGAUGAGGAAACUGAGGCUUGGAAAGACCCAGGUCCUUGCCCAGGCCCCACACCACACCCAGGAGGGGCGGCGCUGGAGUCCUGCGCCACGUCGCUGUUCUCACCAGGAGGAGGCCCUUGUUUGCUGCGUCCAGCGACCCCAUCUCCAUGCUGCAGGCAGGAGGACACAGCCGGGGGUGAGCCAUGAGCGAGGCCUCACGGGGAAGCGAGAGCAGCGGUGUUGCCAUCUGGAUGUCAGACGCGCUCACUUGCUUCUGCCGCACACGGGACUCUGAGCCAGGCCUUAAGGUUUUGGCUCCCUGGGUGUGGCACCCAAGGGGGUGGCCAGGUGGGGUGGAGUGUGAGUUUGAGUGAUUUGGCAUCCCCGUGGAGAUGAUAGGGAGAAUGAGUACCUGUGUCUGCAGCUGCAGAGCGAGAUCCGGGCUGGACGUAGACAUGGGGAGCCACACAGUGGAGGUGGCCUGCUUCUGUUUGCAGCUACAACAAAUCACCAGGACCUCAGCAGUGGGAAUGUCCAGACACGUGAUCGGUUCUCACUGGACUUGGUUAUCCAGGUCCUGUGGGCUGAAGUCUAGGCGUCGGCAGGGCUGGGUCCUCCUGGAGACUCCAGGGGAGAAUCCGUUCCCUGCCUUUUCCAGCUCCUGGAAGCCUCUCGCGUUCCUGGGCUAGGGAACCUUCCUCCAUCUCAGAGCCGGCCAUGGGGUGUCCCCUGACCUUCCGCAGCCAUGUCCCCCUUCGAUGGAGCUCUGCUUCUGGCCCUCCCUCCACACUGAAGGCCCCUGUGAUCACAUGGCCCACCCGCCAAUCCAGGUGGCCUCCCUCCAAGGUCAGCCGGUGAGCUGCCUUCAUGCCUGCAUGGUGUCUCUGACCCUUGGCCACGCAACCUAACAUAGUCACAGGUCCUGGAGAUUUGCACUGGGAUAUCUUGGGUGAGGGGAAUUAUUCUGCUGACCCCCGAUGGCAACUGCAGUGGUGGGAGGGGAAGAGAACACCAGGAUGUGUUCAGAGAGAGAGGCGUGGACCUCAGGGGGUGUCAGGGGAAGAGGGCCCGGGAGGGAGAAAGCAUUUGGUUUAGACGUGUUGGGUGUGAGGUGCCCAUGGAAUAGCAGGGUGGAGCUGGUGGGGGAAGCUGGGGGGCUGCCCUGGGGCUCUAGCACAUGGAGGCCAAGGAGGGAGUCGUGGGGUGGAGGGGGCACAGGGCUCCCCAAGGUCCUGGGUCUGCCUCAGGGCCGCUGCUACUCCACACCCCUCCUCCCAUGCCUGAGCACCCAUGGCAGUGACCAGCAGUGACCAUCAUCACCCAAUGAGGAUGGAGAGAAACUGAGGCUGGCCUGAGAUGUCCUGAGGAAUGAGCUGGCACCAGAGUCCCACAGGUGAAGGGUGAGCAUGGAUGGGCCGGGAGCAUGCUCCCUGUAAUUGUGCAUGGCGCAGAAGGUCAGGAACGGCCUGGUGGCCCCGUGGGAGACUGGUUACUCCAAUCUGGUCCAGCAGAACCCCAGGCAGCCUCGUGGCAGCGUGGGGGAAGUGUCUAUGCUUAGUGAUGUGGCAGAUGCCCGGAGUGCCGUGAGCUUUAAUAACAGUGAGUUACAGAAGUAUGUGAGCCCGUUCCUGAAAACACACACAGUCUGAAAAACGUCCAGAGGGACAGGCCUGAAAAUGUUAAGAGCACUGCAAUCCUGGGGGUUGGUUGUGGAGGUGCUUCCCUUCUCCGUGGUGGUCUGCACUUGCAGUUUCACUGACUGGGAGUCAGAAUAAUGUCCCCCCUCCCCCACAAAAUGCCCACCUCUUAAUCUCUAAAACCUGUACUUAGGACCUUACAUGGAACGGAGACUUUGCAGAAGUGAUUUUGGAUCUGAGAUGGGGAGGUUAUCCUGGCUUGGUGCUGGUCAUUACCCCAAAAGACACAAUCCCAAAAGCCACUAUCCGGAAUGUCAAAAUCCUGAAAGAUCAACAUCCCUAAAGUCUAAAAUCCCUAACAUCUAAUUGAAUCCCUAAACCAUAAUGACAGAUUUGGAAUUCGGCUCAAUCAAGGCUUCUAAAAGCACAUUUCAAGUGUUAGCAAUAAUGUUUGUUUUUUUCCAUUCAGCCCAAUGCAUUUGGCAAAAAAAAAAAAAACAUCCAGAUGAGUGGAUUGGCCAGGCAGUAUGGUAGUGACAAAAACUUCGAUUUAAAACUGCAUUAUUUGCCUGCACCGGCAUUUCUUCCAGCUGAUGAAAUUCUAGGAGAGUCCAUGUCCUAAAGGAUAAGAAGCAACUAUUCGUUGAGAUGAGAGACUUCAAAGAUAGUCAAUGAUCGUGAAAGUCGGCCAGCCUUUCUGGACCAUCUCGUGCAAUUGCUCUAAUCUAUCCCUGCAAUAGAUCCCUUUAAUACACUUUGUCAUAUGUUGAAUUUUCUUUUUAGUUUUUAGUUUUCUUUUGUUGUUGUUGUUGUUUUCCCAUUUUUUAAAAUUAUUAUUAUUGUGGAGACAGAGUCUCACUCUGUCACCCAGGCUGGAGUGCGGGGGUGCGAUCUCGGUUCACUGCACCCUCUGCCUCCCAGGUUCAAGCAAUUCUCCUGCCUCAGCCUCCUGAGUAGCUGGGGCUACAGGCACCCGCCAUUAUGUCUGGCUAAUUUUUGUAUUUUUAGUAGAGACAGGGUUUCACCAUGUUGGCCAGGCUCGUCUCAAACUCCUGACCUCAAGUGAUCCGCCCACCUCGGCCUCCCAAAGUGUUGGGAUUACAGGCGUGAGCCACCACACCCAGGCCCAUUGUUUUUAAUUAUCAACGUUAUUUUUGUUAUUCUAUGUAUUUCAUCUUUGCAUGAUUUCCAGUAUGGGAGGUAUAAAUUGUGUAAAGACGUUGAGAGUUCUAAUUUGUUGUAUGCAUUUUUUACAAAUGUGACUCUGUGAAAAUGAUUAUCACAACAUUGACUUUAUGUGUAAGCGUUGUGUGUGUGCGUACAUAAAAUCGUCGAAACUUCCUCAAUAAAUGAAGAGAUGUCCUUUUUGUACGCCUGAAUUUAUGAAAGGUAAAUUUCUCGAGGUCUUGUUUCUUUGGGCAGCUGCGUGUGCAGUGCUGACCCAUGAGUGUCUGAUCGAUCACGUCACCAGACGUAGGGUGUCCUUCAUGGGUUUUCAAAUGACAGCUGUUAUCUCAGGAAUUUCUUUAUGAAUGUGGUUUGUCUGCUCAUCACCGAGUGUCUAUGCUUGCAAAAAUAUGUCUGUUAUUACUGCCUAUUUUAUUGUGUAAAGUAGCCUGUGAGAUGUUCCAUUGUGUUUUUGUUUCUUAAAUAAAUCUCCUUUAAAAAUGUAAA